GUUCGCUGCGGCGACCAGCUCCGGAAAGCGCGGUGGGGACGCGCUGUGUUCUCGCAGCUCAGAGGCGGGUCUGAGGCUCGGUGGCGGCGCCCAGGGUGGCCCGGGCCCUUUCCUCGGUCGUUGUCUCACCGCCACAGGCUCCGAUGGCGGCGGCCACGCUGAGGGACCCCGCUCAGGGCUAUGUGACCUUUGAGGACGUGGCUGUCUACUUCUCCCAGGAGGAAUGGAGAUUGCUUGAUGACGCUCAGAGGCUCCUCUACCGCAAUGUGAUGCUGGAGAACUUUACACUUCUGGCCUCUCUGGGACUUGCAUCUUCCAAGACCCAUGAAAUAACCCAGCUGGAGUCAUGGGAGGAGCCCUUCAUGCCUGCUUGGGAAGUUGUGACUUCAGCCAUACUGAGAGUUUGGCUGCGUAACAGGUCGGCAAAUCUCCUCACUCAGAUAUUCUUCCCGAACCGACAGCCACAAGUGGCGCCCGAACAGGGACGUGAGUGAAGAAGGUCUGCUGGAGCAGAGAAAGUGAAACUGACCAGAAGAAUGAGAAACCCCAGGACAAGUCUGCUGGCAGUGGAUAUAAGGUCAGUGCCCUAAAGAGGUACUGGGAGUGGGAAGUUUCUGAAUCAGGGUAACAUAGGGCAGAAUUUGUCUGCUGAAGAGCAACAUUAUAUGCAGUCACUUAAAGGUUUACUUAAACAAUCUGGUGCUCAGGUUAGUUCUCAAACACUAGCUAAGCUGCUGCAGGAGGUUAUCACGCAUAACCCAUGGUUUCCACAGACAGACACUCUUGAUGUGGAAAACUGGGGUGAAGAUUUGCUUACGGCAUAGGAUAUGAGACUUACAAAUUAAACUAUUGGCAAUCCAGGAUUUAAAAUGUUAAAGAAAAUGAGAUAUCAGAGCAGACAAGGCUUAGGAAAGUCCCUACAGGAAAACCCUGAUCCUAUAUCAAUAACUGGGCAAACAGAUAGAAAAGGGCUAGGUCGUCAGAUUUCUGAUGUGGGUCAUUGAUAUUUCUCCUCCACCCACUGCUUUGCCACUAGAGUGGCUAACAAACCUGUAUGGGUGGAUCAAUGGCCCCUUUCACAGGAGAAACUAACUCAACUCCAUCAGCUAGUAAAAGAGCGAUUGGAUGCAGGACAUAUUGAAGAGUCAGCCCCUGGAAUUCACCAGUAUUUGUAAUACCAAAAAAGUCAGGAAAAUGGGGACUGCUACAUGAUUUGAGAGCUAUUAAUGCACAGAUUAAACCAAUGGGUGCAUUACAGCAAGGUCUGCCAUCCCUGGCAGGCAUUUCCAAGAGACUGGCCUCUUGUAGUAAUAGAUCUUAUUGUUUUUUUUACUAUACUAUUACAUCAGCAGGAUAGGCCUGGAUAUGCCUUCUCUGUGCCUUCUGUUAAUCAAAGGGAGCCUGUCUCUUGUUAUCAAUGGAAAGUUUUGCCCCAAGGCGUGCUUAACAGUCCUACAUUAUAUCAGAAUUUUGUAGGACAGGCAUUAAAGGAGCCUUGUAAUGUGUUUCCCACUGGCUAUGUCAUUCAUUAUAUGGAUGAUAUUCUUUUGGCCGCUCCUACAGAUCAAAUCUUACAUCAGUUAUUCAGAGAAACAAAACAGGCUUUGACUAAAUGGAAUCUCAAAAUAGCUCCUGAAAAGGUGCAAACCACCUCCCCAUACCAGUACUUAGGCACUAUUAUUACUGAAAGAAGUGUUCAGCCUCAGAAAGUAGUCAUCUGUAGGGACAGAUUACAAACUUUGAAUGAUUUCCAACAAUUAUCAGGGGACAUUAAUUGGCUGCACCCAAUGCUAGGUAUUGCUACUUAUUAACUCAAACACCUUUAUCAGACCCUCCAAGGAGAUUCUUCAUUAGACUCUCCUCGGCAACUUACUAAGGAGGCAGAAGCUGAAUUAUAGCUUGUAGAACAGAUGCUUCAGCAACAACAUGCCACCUGGUUACAGCCACAAAAGCCUUUGCUUCUGUUUAUUCUUCCUACCUCCCAUUCUCCAACAGGACUUUUAGGCCAAUUCAUACACAAAUCUGUAAUAGUAUUAGAAUGGCUUUUUUAUCCAAUCAGACAGUGAAAUCUUUGCAAAUUUAUCUUUCUUUAAUUACUCAACUUAUAACAAUAGGUAGGCAUAGAUCAAAAAUGUUUAUGGGAUGUGAUCCAGACAAAAUUAUUGUUCCCUUGGAUUCCCAACAACAGGCCACAGCAUGGGAAAUGUCGACUGCAUGGCAAAUCACUCUCACAGAUUUUGUAGGAAUAAUAGAUAACCAUUAUCCAUCAGACAAAAUUUUGCAAUUUUAUGAAGUUCACCCUUUUACCCUUCCUGUAAUCACUCAUCACAAGCCUAUUCCAGGCAGACAGACCUAUUUUACUGAUGACUCUUCUAAAGGCUGUGCAGCUAUUUAUGGACCUAAGCAUACUGAAACAAUAAAGACCUCUGGAGUUUCAGCUCAAUGCUCAGAAUUAGUGGCAGUUAUUCAAGUUUUACAGCUCACCGCUUUAUCUCCUAUUAACAUUGUCUGUGAUUCAGCCUAUAUUGUAAAUGUAGCCAGUCACAUUGAGACUGCCACUAUUAAAAGCACCCUAGAACCAGAGCUGUAUAAUUUGUUUCUAAGACUUCAACAAGCUGUUCACUCUCAUGCUGCUCCUUUUCAUAUUUCUCAUAUUUGCUAUCACACACAACUUCCUGGACCACUAUCUCUAGGUAACAAUAAAGCAGAUAAACUAAUCGGUUCUGUAUUUCAACAAGCCCAAUCUUCUCAUGCAUUCCUGCAUCAAAACACCUCUGCCCUUACUCGUAUGUUUCAUCUGCCUUGCAGCCAGGCUUGAGCUAUUGCGCAAGCCUACCCCACUUGCCAGCCUGUCCCUGGCGUUGCACCCAUGGAAGGAUGUAACCCACUAGGCUUGGCUCCAUAUGAAAUCUGGCAGAUGGAUGUUACACAUAUAGCAGCCUUUGGCAAACUCAGCUAUGUUCAUGUGACUACAGACACUUACUCCCAUAUGCUACAUGUCACGUGCCAAACUGGGGAAACAGCUGGUCAUGUCUGAUGACAUUGUCUGUCACCUUUUGCCCAUAUGGGGGUCCCUACACAAUGAAAAACUGACAAUGGACCUGCUUAUGUUAGUCAUGCUUUUCAAAAUUUUUUACAGUUAUGGGCAAUCACUCAUAAAACAGAAAUUCCUUACAAUCCUCAAGGACAAGGAAUCAUAGAGUGGGCACAUCAAACAUUACAAUGCAUGUUGAAAAAACAAAAAUGGGGACUAGGAGACCAGCUACCACCUCAAACAAAAUUACAUUUAGCCUUAUUUACUUUAAAUUUUUUGACUCCUGGUAUGGAUAUUAAGACUCUGGCAGAAUGACAUUGGCAAAUGUUAGAGGGAAAAAGGAAAGUUUACCCAAAGGUAUUACAGAAAUCCCCGGAAGAAGGACAAUGGAAAGGCCCGGUAGACUUACUGAUAUGGGGACGAGGGUUUGCUUGUGUUUUUACAGGAGAUGGACAAUCCGUGUGGGUGCCCUCAAGGUGUGUGUGACCAUGGAACGGGAGACUGGAGAAAUCCAUGGAUCUCAACUGUGGGCCCAGCUCCUCCAGUACGAGCCAUGAGCUAGUUGAAUCUGAAUGCAAAGACAGAACAAGGACCGACUGGAGUCACACUGACAUCAACCCCCAUAAAAUGGGGACAGCUCAAGAAAACCACACAGGAAGCUGAGAAACUGCUGGAGCAAAACCCCUGACUCCAUGUUUAUGGCCAUGCUAGCUGUAAUAUCCUGUGCGGUAUGUUUUCCCUGUGCAGAGGCAAAAACUUAUUGGGCAUAUAUUCCUAACCCACCAGUAGUACGACCGGUACUCGGGAGCAACACUCCUCCUGAGAUAUAUCAUGAUCAGGGAGCAUGGACACCAGGACCCCUAACUCCCCCUGACAGAGAGUGAUUAGAUUCUCAGAACAAUGGUAUCAAUUAUACUGCACCAUUGGAGGGACUUCUUUAUGUGUCACCCAGGAUGCAUCACUCAACCGCAGUUGCCUUGCAAUUCAGUCCCAAGCAUGCUUGAGUUACCAUGGAAAAAUUAUGUACCUAUUAGGCCUUAGCUCUAUUAAUAUUACUGGUGUAGUUACUAAUCACUCCUGGCCCCAUCACCCAAAUUGUAUUGAUUGUACAGAAUGGGCUCCCUUUGAUAAUUCUCACCCCUGUCCUUGGACUCAGUGUCUUGGCCCCUUAGCUAAACAACAGUCCAUGUUAAUGGGAGACAUUAUCGACUGGGGUCCCCAUGGUCAUUUAGAUGGGAGAAGUGAGAAUCAGACCUCAUGGCAUAAAUUUUGCUGGCACUGGUGGCGAAACUUGAACAUCUCUUCGCUACAUCCCAAUCUGCUACACAACUUGCUUGGCACAGAAUGGGCUUUAGCCCACCUUUGCCUCAAUGGCAUUAUCAAGGAAAGAGAGGUCCAAUUCAGGAGUCAAUAUGGAAGACAGCACUCCCAUUUAUGAAUGGCAGCAUUUGGGUUGGGACACUAUCCAAUAAUAGUAAUAAUGCUCAAUGCAGUUUUAAUGUUACCUUUGUAGAAAAUACUACCACACAGUUUACAAUUUGUAUUUUUAAUCCGUAUGUUUUUCUAGCAGCAAAAAAGGACCAACUCCGGGUAAACAAUGCCCAAUCGAUUUGUGAUGCCUGUCAACUGUAUCAUUGCCUUAAUCAUAGCACAAUACAAACACACAGCAUAUCCACCCUAAUAAUUCUAGGUCACAUUCCUGGAUUAUAGAUUCCUGUAAAUCUGUCCGAGCCUUGGGAGGCCACCCCCGCUUUACAUUUUGUAAAACUCCUUCUUAUUCAGCUUACUCAUCGUGCUCGUAGAGCUUUAGGCAUGAUAAUUUUUGCUAUAAUUUCCCUAGUCACACUAAUAACCUCUGCUGUGUUGUCCUCAGUAGCACUGCACAGCUCCAUUCAAACAGCUCAAUGUGUGAAAAAUUGGAUGUGCACAGCCGACCAGGAAUGGAUGCUUCAAAAUAAAAUUAACACCAAGAUACAAACAGAAGUGGCAAUGUUAAAGACUACUGUUCUGUGGCUAGGAUAACAAAUACAAAGCCUGAAGUUGCAGCAGCAAUUGCAUUGUCAUUUUAACCCUAUUCAUAUUUGUGUAACUAAUUUGGAAUAUAAUCAAAGUGAAUAUCCAAGGAACUUUGUAAAGGCCCAUUUACAGGGAGUUUUACAUUCAAUGUUACUUUUGAUAUUAAUGAUUCACAAAGUAAAAUCCUUAACUUGAAUAAGCAGACUCAAGUGCUUCAGCCCUCUUUAAAAGCUUGGGCAGAAUUCCAGCAAGGUUUAGGGAGCCUUAACCCUUGGACCUACUUCAAACAGCACCUCAAUGUCUUUUUUGUGAUUAUCGGAAUAAUGUUAUUAUGUUUCUGUUUUUUGUUCAUAGUCUGUAAAAUCAGCUGGACCACCAACCGGCAAUUGAGAGCUGCACAGCCUGCAAUUACCUUUAUUCAAUUAAUACAAAAACAGAAAAGGGGGGAGGUUGGAGGCCGAAAGAAUGAGGGUCGUGACCAACUCAGUAUACCACUGGAGGCUAUAUGAGCAAACAGCAAACUGUUCUCAUGAAUGCAGGAUGCUGGCAAGCUGACAACUGCAUCUGCCACCAGAAGGAAUGCUGAGGGCAGUCAUACCCCACGUGCAGUGUUCCUUGUGGUUAUCUAUAGGAACAUCUGGAGGCUGUUGUAUAAAGAAAGCAAUUAUGUGAGCCUGUGAUAAAUCAAGCAGCUGACCAACCAUUACCUCUUCCUCCCUGUUGAUUCUACCUAAUAAAUACAAAGGGCUGUAGAAGCUCAGGGCCCUUGUUCCCUAGAAGAAAGGAGCCGCCUGUCUCCUUCUUUAAAACAGA